AGGUGUUUGGAGAGCCCGGACUGGAUGCCCACUAGAAUCCUGUGCUGUGAACAGUGAGAGAGUUUUCUUCAUUUUGAGGAACCCUAAACACCUAUCUUUCCCAAGGCAACCUGUCUGGACUGAGCAUUUCUCUGACUUGACAUAACUUCCCAUCCAGCCAGGAGUCUGCACUCUUCAGUCUUUGCAGAUAACUUUUAAGUGGUGAAGAGUAUAAAUCGUGGUUUUCCAAGUGUAGUCUAAGGUCUAACAGCAUCGGGGAUAUCUGGGAAAUUAUCAGAACUACAGACCCUCUGGCUGCACCCCAAACCUGCUGAAUCGGAAAUUCUGAGGCAGUAGCAGAAUCCCAUGGUAGCCAGGUGGGUGAAGGGGAGCGAGGACGUUCUACCUGCCUUGAAGAAGACACCUGACCUGCGGAGUGAGUGACCAGUGUUUCCAGAGCCUGGCAAUGGAUGCCAUUCACAUCGGCAUGUCCAGCACCCCCCUGGUGAAGCACACUGCUGGGGCUGGGCUCAAGGCCAACAGACCCCGCGUCAUGUCCAAGAGUGGGCACAGCAACGUGAGAAUUGACAAAGUGGAUGGCAUAUACCUACUCUACCUGCAAGACCUGUGGACCACAGUUAUCGACAUGAAGUGGAGAUACAAACUCACCCUGUUCGCUGCCACUUUUGUGAUGACCUGGUUCCUUUUUGGAGUCAUCUACUAUGCCAUCGCGUUUAUUCAUGGGGACUUAGAACCCGGUGAGCCCAUUUCAAAUCAUACCCCCUGCAUCAUGAAAGUGGACUCUCUCACUGGGGCGUUUCUCUUUUCCCUGGAAUCCCAGACAACCAUUGGCUAUGGAGUCCGUUCCAUCACAGAGGAAUGUCCUCAUGCCAUCUUCCUGUUGGUUGCUCAGUUGGUCAUCACGACCUUGAUUGAGAUCUUCAUCACCGGAACCUUCCUGGCCAAAAUCGCCAGACCCAAAAAGCGGGCUGAGACCAUCAAGUUCAGCCACUGUGCAGUCAUCACCAAGCAGAAUGGGAAGCUGUGCUUGGUGAUUCAGGUAGCCAAUAUGAGGAAGAGCCUCUUGAUUCAGUGCCAGCUCUCUGGCAAGCUCCUGCAGACCCACGUCACCAAGGAGGGGGAGCGGAUUCUCCUCAACCAAGCCACUGUCAAAUUCCACGUGGACUCCUCCUCUGAGAGCCCCUUCCUCAUUCUGCCCAUGACAUUCUACCAUGUGCUGGAUGAGACGAGCCCCCUGAGAGACCUCACACCCCAAAACCUAAAGGAGAAGGAGUUUGAGCUUGUGGUCCUCCUCAAUGCCACUGUGGAAUCCACCAGCGCUGUCUGCCAGAGCCGAACAUCUUAUAUCCCAGAGGAAAUCUACUGGGGUUUUGAGUUUGUGCCUGUGGUAUCUCUCUCCAAAAAUGGAAAAUAUGUGGCUGAUUUCAGUCAGUUUGAACAGAUUCGGAAAAGCCCAGAUUGCACAUUUUACUGUGCAGAUUCUGAGAAACAGCAACUCGAGGAGAAGUACAGGCAGGAGGAUCAGAGGGAAAGAGAACUGAGGACACUUUUAUUACAACAGAGCAAUGUCUGAUCACAGGGGCGCCAUCCAGGUUUAACCCUGCAAGCUGUUUCCACAUCAGAACUCCCUUCAAACACAAAGAUUGCUGUGAAAACGAAAAUGUGUAGACGCACUCUCAAAAACUGCACGGACAUACAAAAUCAAUCUUUUCCUUUGAUCUUGUGGCUAAACCAGCAUUUCUGUGUUUGAGAGAUUUCCUGUUAGGUGCUUCGUCUGAAAGUGAACUCUCAUAAUUCAAAUUGUAUAAAAUAAAGCUACAUUUCUAAGAGCUUGGUGUAGGGCAAUUGGAAUAAUGUCCUGUUAGAUAAACAGACAUUUAGCAAUCCUGACAUUAAAAGGAAAUGUAUUUCUAUACAAGAUUAUUAGCUGUAAUACAAGAUAUUUAUUUAACCAAUGACCUUAUGGCUGAGAGUUGAAUUGUGGUUCAGUAUUCAUUGAUCUCACUGCUUUAAAACAUGCUCUUUUUGUUCAAGCAGGAAAAAUAUUAUAUCUAAUUAUGUCUAUGUGGUAAUACCUAAAAAGAGGUAGAGAGACUCUAUGUUCACAAAAUAUAGUAAUUUCAUUUUUACCUUUCUUCAGUGGACUGAAUUGUAUGGAAGGAAAUUGAUCAGAUCUGUAAUUCACAACUGUGGAAACCUACACAAAUGGGGCUGAUGCCAUUGUUUCCUCUAUUUUAUUUUAUUUAUUUUUGAAUCCACUAUCUCUUUCCAUUCAAAAUAUUUCCAUUCAAAAUGUGGUUCACAGACCCGCCACAUCAGCACCAUCCGAGAGCUUAUUAGUAAUGUGUAGAUUCUCAUGUCCCAGCCAGACUUACAGAAUUGGGGUCUGUAUCUUAACAAGAACCCCAGAUGAUUUGUGUACAAAUGAAAGUUCGAAAGCUGUGCUCUGGACAGUGUUCUCAAAGCAACUUUCUGAAGCCGUGUGGAAAACUGACUCUGUGUGGGUCCCGUAUCCCUGUGGCAUCCAGACCUGGCCUCUCUUCAUUUCAUUAUUAUUGGCCAAUAUUUCUUUCAGCCAUUUCAUUUCUUAUCUAUUAAAAUGGCUUGCCCAUAAAGGAACUGCAUAGGAUUAUCCCCUGACAUUCCAAGAGCAAAAUAAAGCUCUUGAGAGUAAUUGUUGUCUCAGUCAUGCUUGCUGAUUACAGUUAGCACAAAAGAAAAAUUCAGCUGCCUGACAAUACAGGAAAUGUUCUCAGAUGCUGAUGUUUGUAAGGUCCGGUGGGGCCAUGAGGAAGAAGAGGAGCUGAAGGUAAGAAACUCAUAAACAAGAUGACUCUUUGAUGCAUGAACAAGAUUUGAAAAUCUCAAGCCUGUAAAGAAUACCCCUGCUAUUUAAAUAAAGCUCAUACCAAGAGGUAACAUUUUGCCCCGGGCCAAAUUCAGGGGUCUAGUGCCCUGCAUUCCUUUGAGGCAAAAAAUAAAUGGGCUAUGACUGGUUAAAUGUCCAAAAGGUGAAUUCUCAUUUCAUUCAAACAAAGACAGAUUUGCGCAUUCACUCAAGCAGAAUGUGGCCAUGAAUAUUCAGCCCCUGCAUACAUACAAAGAUGUACGCAUGAUUCCCCCCACCAAGCACACACACAGUCACACACGCACACACACACACAUGCACACACGCGCGUGCACACACGCACACAUGCACACACACAUACGCACACGUAAACACAUGCACACAUGCACACACGCGCACACAUGCACACACGCACACACUUGCACAGGCCCUGGCUCUUCAAGCAUAAUCAUGGUAGUCAUCAGUGAAAGACAUUUGAGGUUAAGACAGCAAGUCCUUGACAAAUAUGUUCAUGUCUAUUUGGUUCUAGUUCUAUAAAAAUAUGAACAUUGGGACUCAGAGAAAAUGGGGAAAAUAAAGUGGAUUCAGGUUAUCAGUGAAAUGAUGGUAUAGAUUACAGCAAAUCUGGAUAUAUAUUGAUGUUACUGCAUUUGCAAAUGUCCUCCCAUUAAACAGAAAAUGUGGCUAAAAUCCCUGGCCUGGAACUGAACUAGUUUAAGGCAGGUGUAAGAAUAGUGGGAGGAAAGUUUGUGAAAGUUUAAAGAAUGCCCUCAAUCCAUGAACGAGAGGGAGGAUGUUGUCUUUAAUUAUUUAGAAGGUUUUUUUUUCCUUGUCUGUUGAUAAUUUUAUGGAAGGUUGCUUUAGAUCUCCAUUCCUUAAAAAAAUAUUACAUGUCAGUGUAGUUAGAUAUUAUCUCUUUUAGUUAUUAUACUUGCUAUUUUUACUGUAUAGUGUGGUAUAAUCAACAAAAAAUAAUGCCACGGGCAUGUUUACACCUUUUCUGUUGCACUAUUAAAUUCUUUUCACAGUAUUCAUAUCAAUGCUAAUUUGAAUGUGAUGCCAAUUAAAAAUCUUGUUCAUUUAUAUUGUAUAUGGUACAAGGACGUAGCAUAAGAUCCAAAAAAAAUUUUGUAUUGUCAUUUAGCAUAUCAAUUUCAGCCAAAUUUGGAAGACUUGAUCAUCUUAUCUUUUGCUCUACACACUCAAAACAAAUAUUGCAGCAGAAAUAUCACCUUAAAAAUAUCUUAUUUUAUAUUUAGAUAAUAUUGAAAUCACAGUCUAUUAAAAUUGGAAAUUUAAUUCAAAUAAAAAUCAAACAAAAUAGUUGUUUCAAUUUAUCUAAAUAUCUGGUCUUAAGAGUGCCUUAAGAGUGUCUCGUUUUUAAGAGUGUCUUAAAAACCAAUAUAUGUAUAAGUCAACAAAUCAUAUAAUAUUCAAUAAAUAGCUCUGAAGUUGUAUCUGAUUUGAAACUUACCAUUUUCCUGGAACCUUAACUAUUAUUACUUUGUACGUAAUACUUUCAUGUUACUAUGCUAACAAAGGAUUUAGGUAGCCAACUUAAUUUAUUAUAUCUGGUCGGUCUUCUGCUUGAAACAGAUUCACACUCAACACCCAACUAAGGAGGAGCCAAAGUAGUGGAGUAUUCCUGACCCAAAAAGGCUUUUGAAUUUUGAAACAUUUCUAAUGUGUUAGGUUUUCUCAAUGAGACCAUUAAAAAACGUUGUGUUCCAUUUGAGAAACCAGAGUCAACAGCAGUAAAUCAGUGUGCCCCACAAGCCACGUCUUAUUCAGCAAUAAAAUAGUGCUCACAUGGUGCCUGGCAGACAGUGGCUCUGGACAGCAAAGCACUGAGUCACCCAACCCCACUCCUUUGGGAUGGGGUUGGGAGUCAUGCAUUGGCUCCCUUUUUCAUCCUGGGGAAAUUACAACACAACGCAGAGUGUCCAGAAAUCUAAAGAGCUGGUUUAAGGUGAAAAAAAUGCCAUGAAUGAAUGAACCAGAUGUUUAAUAAAUCAAAACAACUAUUUUGUUGGAUUUUUAUUUGAAUUAAAUUUCCCAAUUUUUAAUAGACUGUGAUUUCAAUAUUAUCGAAAUGUAAACAAAGAUAUAUUUUUAAGGUGGCAUUUCUACUCCAGCAUGAAAAAAAUAGUGGCAUUUGCACUCUAGCAUUAUUCUGUCUCCCUUAUUUGAGUCUUCAAUAUAUAUGCCCAGCUGGAGGGAGAAGAAGAGAAAAAUGAAAGCACUAGGCCUUUGACUAGGUUUGGUUCUAUAUGCUGUCAUGAUGUUCAAAAUGUCAGACAUUUGACCACAUGGCACAGUGAAUACUCUCACGCUCUCAAUUUUGGCUUUCAUUCUUGCUAGACUUUUCUUCUAUUAAAUUUCUGAAAUAACUAGUUUUUUUUUUUUGAACUUGAAAAUCAGCUUUUUAUUUUUUUUAAUUUUAUUAUUAUUAUACUUUAAGUUUUAGGGUACAUGUGCACAACGUGCAGGUUUGUUACAUAUGUAUACAUGUGCCAUGUUGGUGUGCUGCACCCAUUAACUCGUCAUUUAGCAUUAGGUAUAUCUCCUAAUGCUAUCCCUCCCCCCUCCCCCCACCCCACAACAGUCCCCGGUGUGUGAUGUUCCCCUUCCUGUGUCCAUGUGUUCUCAUUGUUCAAUUUCCACCUAUGAGUGAGAACAUGCGGUGUUUGGUUUUCUGUCCUUGAGAUAGUUUGCUGAGAAUGAUGGUUUCCAGUUUCAUCCAAUAACUAGUUUUAUCAUAGCUUUCCAUGAUGUAAUUUUUUAAGCGAAAGGUACUAACAUUUCCAGUCUUGAUUUCCAAGUUUUGUGGUGUGCACUCGAAAUCUAGUCUCUGAUUGUUAAACUCUGGGUAGGUACAAGAGGCUCUUAAUUUUCUUCCUCCCAGGAGGACUUACUUACACUUAAAGGUCAAAAGCUUAACAUUCACUUCUAAAUGGUUAACUGCAUACACUUUACCCUUUGUAAACUUCAAUUUAUCUUUUUUUUUUUUUUUUUUUUUUUUUUUUUUUGAUACUGGGUCUCGCUCUGUCGCCCAGGCUGCUAGAGUGCAGUGGCGCGAUUUCGGCUCACUGCAAGUCCGCUUCCAGGUUCACGCCAUUCUCUCCCUCAGCCUCCCGAGUAGCUGGGACUACAGGCGCUCGCCACCAUGCCCGGCUAAUUUUGUUUUUGUGUUUUUAGUAGAGACGGGGUUUCACCGUGUUAACCAGGAUGGUCUCGAUCUCAUGACCUCGUGAUCUGCCCGCCUACAAGCCAGGUGUGGUGGUGCGUGCCUGUAAUCCCAGCUACUCAGGAGACUGAGGCAGGAGAUUCGCUUGAACCCGGGAGGUGGACGUUGCAGUGAGCUAAGAUCGCGCCACUGCACUCCAGCCUGGGCAACAAAAGUAAAACUCCGUCUCAAAAAAAAAAAAAAAAAGAAAAAGAAAAAGAAAAGAAAAGAAAAUAAACGUGGCAAAACUAGACCUUCAGACACUUCACUUCACUUAACCCUAUGGCCCUCCUUAUCUUGCACCCAAUUUCUUUUCAACAUCAUACAUGCUUGGUUGACUGUUUCUUCAUAUUUGCUGUUCAUUCUAUAAAGUCAAAUAGAUUGGUGGGUUAAAAAAUAAUCAAUUCAAAUUCAAAUUAGGAAUUUAUGGACAUUCAGAUAUCCACAUAUUUGAGGGCAGGAAUUUUUACUUUUCAAUUGGUAUGUUGGCAGUGUGUAAAAAUAGAAGACCAAGAGAAGGCGGUUGAUUGGAGUUGAUACUUAAUAGCUAAUAAAAAUUACAAGAAAGGAUGGUGGAAGUCAAAGGACAGAACUGAUACACGAGUAUAAAAGCCAACGAUGUCAUAUAUGUAGGCAAAGUCUUUGUAAUCUGAAUAUAAUGCCAGAGAGCUAGGGCUGCCAGGCACUCUGUAUGUGCAGAAUAUGUCCUAUAUGGAGUAAUUUUUUAUUUGUGUAGACUUUUUUAGGAUACCUUAAAUGUCUUACAUGCAACCUUUUUUUCCCCAUAUAUUACAAAAUUGCCUUGGAAAUUAGACAAAUCUUCAAACUUAACUGAAACUCCUGUCCUGAAUAGUUAUUUGCCAAAUCUGACAAAUUUACAAAGAGUGUUCACAUAAUCCCAAACUAUGCCCAUUUCUACAAGAGAAAUACAUGCCUCUUUAUUUGGAGUUUAUGAUAUUCAUACAACUAGUAGUAGAGUCAGGGAGUAUUCCAGAAACAUAUUUCCCUGGCUUGCCCAAUUAUCAAGGGAAAAUUUCAGCUGAACACGGGGAACCCAGUCUUUGACACUCCUGUGUGCAGUGUGGAGCAGCGUGCACUGUCUGAGUCUCCAUAGUGAGGAAUGGUCUUCCCUGGGGCAUCACCCUAGAAGGAUGGGCUCAAAGUCGCCCUCCACGUGGGUGCACAGGAGCCCAGAUUCUCAAGCCCCAGUUGCAGAAUUAGGCUGAUGGUUUUACAAAAGAGUCCUCCUAAAAGUCCAUCACUAAGUUUUGUUUGGUUAGCAACCCUUGCCACAUGAUGUAGUACUUAGCUAUAAUUUUAUUUUUAUUCAAGGCCAAAUCUUAUCUGGUGUCCAUGCCUUCCCACCUACUUAAAAUUUCAAAUUUCACCCUCAAAAAUAUUUCAGUAAAUAAAAGUUAGAUCUACUCAAAAUUAGACUCCAAGGGAAUUACUAUAGUUGAUUAUAGAGUAUCUAUUUCCUUAAAAAAAAAAAACCAUAAGUUGUUGACUCUGAGCUAGGAAAUGCGUGAUCUCUCAGCUGACUUACUUUAUGCAAAUUUACUUAAUAUUAUAGAAGAGUAAAGAGCUUCCAAGAAGGUGAUUGGAGGGAAGUUCAAAGGGAAGAUUUUUUUCAUUCACUGUAGUUUUAGCUGUAUUCUUUCAUCUGCAAUCAAAUCUCAGGAUUAAGGAUGUCGUAUUACAUCAAAUCAUUACAGGAAGUAUGACUGUAUCAGCGGCUUUUUACAAAAACAAACCUCCAGAUCACAAAAGGAAGCUGUGUUUGUGUACUGACACGAAGUGUUACGUAGCAGCCAGGAGAGGAAGGAUAGCAGCCGACUUGGAUCCAUUUUUGAGGAAUUAUUUCUGUAAGGUGUCAUGGAAUUGUAAGUUACAAAAAUAAGGCUUUUGUAAACAGAAUCUCCAUUCCAGAAGGACGGACUCCAAAAUGCUACUUAAUGAAAUUCAUGGGAAUGUUAUGGUGAUGGAAAUCCCAAAUGACAUGUAGAUUUUAUAUGCAAACAAUCCCACUGCUUGUAACUCCUGGCAGUGUGUACUUACCAAAAUCUUGAUCACACUUAGGUCUCUUGCUAUAUAUAGAACCACAUCUGAUCCUUAUACAGUGUUGCAAGAUAUAUGUCCUUGCUUUCCCAUGGUUCUUAAGUGAGUCUUAAGCUUGGAUUUGCUCCAGCAGAAUGGUGGUUUGUGUUUCUCAAGGCUGAGCUACUAUUUGGUGCAUGUCGGAAAUCUCACACUAACUGUGGAUACUCUGUCAUCACUGAACCCAAUCAUACAAUGACCAGACAGCUUUAAAUACCUACUUUUGUAUGCUAUGAAUUCAUCCGUUUACUUGUCAAAUCCUUUAUUUCCAUAUGUGUCUCCAUCACCUUUUUUUUCUCUCCGGAUAAAUGGAAUUACUGUAACUUGUGAAACAAUGGCAAACACUAUAAAGCUAAUUUUACAGUCUUGA